GUCUUCCCGGCGCCCAGGCUUGGGCUCAUAGGGAGAAAGGAAGCUGCGCUGCAUUCUGCGGGACGAACCCUGCUCCGCGCGAGAAUUUUUUUGAUUCCUUCUUAUUUGGAGAAAUCUCCAGCUGCUCUGAUGAUAGCCUAAGAAGACUGCAUGCUGCUUCCUCUCGAUGCCAAGCCAGACCCUCUCACAACCUCGGAUCUCAGUCCUUCAUGGAGACCUGGUCCCAGCAGGAAUGGCAGUGCAGGAAAUUGGCGCCCAGAUGGUUCUUCCAUGUGAAGUUGUCUCGGGCUCUGGGCUGACGAGAGAACACCUGGUAACCAGGUUAGCCCUCUGUCAGUCACCCAGGGCAGGGCAGCAUGGUGCGGAUUCAGAGGAGGAAGCUUUUGGCAUCUUGCCUGUGCGUCACAGCCACCGUCUUUCUGCUUGUCACACUCCAGGCCUUGGAUACCGUUGAGAAUCUAAUGAAAGUCACGGGCCCUCCCCAGGGAGUUACAGACUCCAUGCAAUGCUUCAAUGAUCAGCGGCCUUUAUCUAACACCAGGAGCAGCGAGCACAUAAAAGAGGUCAUGGUUGAGCUGGGGAAGUUUGAAAGGAAGGAGUUUAAAAGUUCCAGUUUGCAAGAUGGACAUACAAAAAUGGAGGAAGCACCUACGCAUCUUAAUUCAUUUCUUAAGAAAGAAGGAUUGACCUUCAACAGGAAAAGAAAAUGGGAAUUGGACAGCUACCCCAUUAUGCUCUGGUGGUCCCCGCUGACGGGGGAGACUGGGAGGUUAGGCCAAUGUGGAGCAGAUGCUUGUUUCUUCACCAUCAACCGGACCUACCUCCAUCAUCACAUGACCAAAGCAUUCCUCUUCUAUGGUACUGACUUUAACAUAGAUAGCUUACCUCUGCCUCGGAAAGCCCAUCAUGACUGGGCUGUUUUUCAUGAAGAGUCCCCGAAAAACAAUUAUAAGCUCUUUCAUAAACCAGUGAUCACCUUGUUCAACUACACUGCCACGUUCAGCAGGCAUUCCCACUUGCCACUAACUACCCAAUACUUGGAGAGCAUUGAAGUCCUGAAGUCACUCCGAUACCUAGUUCCUUUGCAGUCCAAAAACAAGCUUAGAAAAAGACUUGCUCCGCUGGUGUAUGUACAGUCAGACUGUGACCCACCAUCAGACAGGGACAGCUAUGUUCGCGAGCUGAUGACUUACAUCGAGGUCGAUUCCUAUGGUGAAUGUUUACGAAACAAAGACCUCCCUCAGCAGCUGAAAAAUCCAGCCUCUAUGGAUGCCGAUGGCUUUUAUAGGAUCAUUGCACAGUAUAAGUUUAUCCUAGCUUUUGAGAAUGCAGUUUGUGAUGACUACAUCACUGAGAAGUUCUGGAGGCCACUGAAACUGGGGGUAGUCCCUGUAUAUUACGGAUCCCCCAGCAUCACAGACUGGCUUCCAAGUAACAAAAGUGCUAUUCUUGUAUCAGAAUUUUCUCACCCCAGGGAACUGGCAAGUUACAUCAGACGACUGGAUUCUGAUGACAGAUUGUAUGAGGCCUAUGUAGAAUGGAAGCUGAAGGGUGAGAUCUCUAACCAGCGACUUCUGACAGCUCUCAGGGAACGGAAAUGGGGAGUGCAAGACGUCAACCAGGACAAUUACAUCGAUGCAUUUGAGUGUAUGGUGUGCACCAAGGUGUGGGCUAAUAUCAGGCUUCAGGAAAAGGGCUUACCACCCAAAAGAUGGGAGGCAGAAGAUACCCACCUGAGUUGCCCAGAGCCCACAGUGUUUGCUUUCUCACCACUCCGGACUCCACCUUUGAGCUCUUUGCGAGAGAUGUGGAUUUCCAGCUUUGAACAAUCCAAGAAAGAAGCCCAGGCACUAAGCUUAUUGGUAUUUGGCAAACCUGGUAUCCUGCAGCCGAGCAUGAACAUGAAAUACAUUAGAACUUGGCAAUGAGAGAUCCCAUCUGUUGGUUUCCAGGGAUGUAAGUGAGUAAUAAAAGCUGUUUCAAGUUUAUCCACUAUCCACUCUUCAAGUGAAAAGAACUUAUGUGUGUCUACCUUCUUCUCCAUACCCUGAGCCACCUCUCUCACUUUCUUUAGUUGUGCCUUGCCCUAUCGCCUCCCAUUUUCCCUUCAAAGUAGAAUGUCUUGUAAAGACACAGUAACUCCUGUGUGUUUUGAUUAGUGAGAUGUUACCACUUACCCCUUCUGCUGCGCAGAAUAAUAUUAAGAAUUGCUAUGCUUAUGAUUCAGGCUGGACAGCCUGGACAUUUUGAGCAGCGCGAGAGUAGAAGUGAAUACCCCCAGGAACUCCAAUUGUGCUGAAGCUGAUUUGUCUGUUCGUAGGAUGAUGUGCAGCCUGUCACAGUGGCAGCCACAGGCAUUCAGUUUGUGGGCAUUUCCUGUCAUUUCGGAUCCUGCUAUAGGGAAGGUUCAGCUCUCCUGUCUGGGGCAUCUACUGGAGCACCUCAGAAGACAAGGAGGAAAACACUGGCUCAUGUUUUCUUUCCAUGUGAGGGAGGGGAGGUUUCUAGAUGAUACUAAAAGCCUGUUGCCACUGUUGUGUCAUGAUUUCCAUUCUUCAUCAUGGAAAGCCACAAGCCUCAGAAGGCAGCCAGAGGACAGGAAGAGUCUGUGAUGCUCAUGUCUGUGUCAUGGCAUGAGGGGGAAUUGACGAGUGCUUGCUUAGCAUCAGCUCUCAUUGUAUUGAAGGCUGUGCCCUUGGUGUGCUUAGCAGUGAGCAGCGUCUUCAUUAGGUAGCUCUGGCUGGGCUUUGUCAGCCAGCGUGUGAGAAAGGAGAACCAAAACCAAUACCUCCUUAUAGAAGCCAGAAGGAUCACAUUGGAUGAGAGAAGGUGUCUAUAACUGGGUUCUUCCCAAUCCCAGCUCUUUCAUUAACUAAAUAUGAUCUUGGACAUAUCUCUUAACCUCCAUCGGCCUUAGUUUUUGCAUCCAAAAAGAAGUGAUUGGGCUGGUCUUGGAAGGUUUUUUUCUUUUUUUUCCCCUGUGUAACAUUCUUCAUUGUUCAUCAACAUUUAAGAAAUUUAAUUUUGUAGAUGUUUUUACUAAAGAGGGUAACAAACUAUUUUGGAACUGCUGUAUGUUAUUCAAGGGAAGCACGCUGUUUGGAGGAAGGAGCAUACUUAAUGGGUAGUAUUGAGGAUGAAAGGGAAUUUCUCUCUCUGCCAUUUUAUUUGAUAAUAUUAAAGAAAUAAAGACUGGAAAGGGGGAUUCCUUGUUAAAGGUCAGAUUUUAAAUUGCAUAUAAAAUGAAGUGAGUUGUGUUUUUUUGAACCCUCAAAAGAAAGCCUGAGAGGUGAUUUAUGCCUCUGGCAAGGUAUUAUCAUGAUAACUUCAGUUCUUCUCCAUAAAUGCCUUCAGCAAAUACCCAGUGCUUAUGUGCUGUGUGUAUGUCUUAAACCUUAACUUUCAUGAAAUCUCAUUCCAUCUUAGUUCUUCAUCAAGUCCAUAGAUAAAAUCCUCUCUAAGCGUUUCUGAAGUAUGUAUCCCUGAACAAAUUUAGUGAAAUAAAAUCAUUAAUCUGUGUUGAUCCCAUUUUGCCAUACCUUUCACUUUACCUCACUGUCUCCUUUUGUGAAAUAUUUUAAGAAAGCAACGUCCCUCACAGGACUGUUUUGAGGAAUGCCUCAUGGCUGUGAAGGAGUUUGUACAAUGCAACAUUUUGCUUAGCCCUUCAGUACAUUUUACUUGGAUUGUUUUCAAGAACUUUAUUUUUUUUGAGAAGAAGUCUUGCUCUAUCACCUAGGCUGGAGUGCAGUGGUGCGAUCUCAGCUCACUGCAACCUCCACCUCCUGGGUUCAAGCGAUUCUUCUGCCUCAGCCUCCCAAGUAGCUGGGAUUACAGGCACCUGCCACCAGGCCUGGACAAUUUUUUUUUUUUUUUUUUUUUUUUUUUUUUUUUUUUAGUAAAGAUGGGGUUUCAGCAUAUUGGCCAGGCUGGUCUUGAAUUCCUGCCCUUAAGUGACCCACCCACCUCGGCCUCCUAAAGUGCUGGGAUUAUAGGCCUGAGCCACUGCGCCUGGCCAUUCAAUGACUAAUUUUUAAAAGCAAUAUUACAAAGUGGUCAGAAGCCUUUUCAGAAAUGUUGGAGAAAAUGAUCACUAAUGCUAGUUAAUAGUCUUCGCCUAAAAAUGAAUGCAACUUUUACCCUUGAUCAUAUAGCAAAUAUAUUUUGGAACCUGAAUGCUGAAUGGCUUCUUUGUUGCUGUUAAGGACUAGAUUCUAGUAACCAGAAUAUCAGUUGGGGUCAUUAUCAUUGUUAGUAAUAGAUUGGAAACAUAUAGUGUUCUAUGCAUUACUCAGAAAUAAGAGACAUAAGCAAAAAUGAACAUCAUUCCUUCAGCCACACAUUGUAUAUUACACAUAGAAGAACCUGCUCAAUAUCUAUAAAAGACUGUAUGAAUUCAAGCACAGUGCCGACCUGCCCAGUAAAAUGCCCAGUAAAAUGUGCAUUAAAAAAGUCAUUAAUAGGACAUAAGUCCUGCUAAAGAUGGCAAUUCAUUAGGACCUCAGGCUGCUGUAACAGAAUACGAUAGACUGGGUGGCUUAUAAGAAACAGAAGUUUAUUGCUCACAGUUCUGGAGCAAAAUAUAAAUUAUGGAAAUUUUCUUUAGGAAAUUUCUUUCUUUUAAUUUUUAUUGUUAAUGGUAAUAUCUUUACUGUGUAAUUCUAAUAUCAGCAUAUAUCUUGUUGUCUUUGAUUACAGACAUAAAAAUGCUUGAAAAACUCAAAGGGGAUAUAGAAUGAUGACUCUAAGAAAUAAUCUAGUUUUAGUUGCUACUCUGCAACAUACUGUCUUUAUUAUCUUGGUCAAGUUAUAUGGCCUUUCUAAGAUUCAGCUUGCUCAUCUGUAAAAUGGAUGUUAUAAUAUCCAACCUCCUUGUGAGGUUAUUGUGAUGAGCUAGUGUUCACUUUGCUCAAUAGAUGCUUGUUGUAGUGGUUACAGCUAUCUGUGGUCAUUACCCUUUGUGUUUGAAGAGCUUGACUGAGAUUUGUCCAGAAAAAGGGAAUCGUUGAUGAUAGUACCUGGGGUGGUACACAUUUAUUGUGUUACAAAAUAGGCAUUGUACUAGGCGCCAUUGCUGAUAGGAAUAAGACACAGGAGAGAGAGGUGUGAAGGGUUUUGAGUAGGGCUUUUUGAUAUUAUGAUGGUAUUAAAACCAAGGACUGAGGAAUGCUUAAAUUAUUCUCUGACUCUUCCCACCCUCCAUGGGAUUUCUGGUGGAGUCUUGCACAAAGCUCUCAAUAGGAUAAUCAGACUCAAACAGCCUCUUUAUAGUAGCUUUGCAAACCACAUAAAUGCAGUACACUGAUUGAUUGUAUAAGCUGGAUCUGAGCAUAUUAUUUAGAUUUGAAGUGUAACUAGGAGAGGAUCUUUUACUGCCUUUCCAUUUCCCAAUUCUGAAUCUUGGGACUAGUCUAUUCAAUGUGCUUGCAAUAAGAAAGAGGAGAGAAAAAUGCCUAGAUCUGUAGGUCUUGACCCUGCUUGCUCAUACUGAAGAUCAACUGAAGAAGGAGAAGAAGAGGAGCCUGAGCAGCCUUUCUCCUAGGAGACAAGCCCUCUCUUGCUGUCCAUGUGAUAUGGAUGCAAGAAUAUGGAGUACAAUGCAUGGGAGCUUACUUUUAAGUCAUAUUAACCUUUUUCACUAGUAAAAUGUGGCCUCAUCUAUAUCCUGGGAUUAAACCAAUUAAUUUAGCAACACCAUUGGUGCUGGUAGUAGGCCCAAUUAAGGAGAUCGGCAAGGGAUAGAGGUGUUUGAGGAGAAGUGACUCUUUAGGAUUAUUGUCCUCUCGAGUCAUUGGACUUAACAGCCAAGCCUCUGGUCAGUCAGAGGUGUGGCUGUAUCCCAAAGAGGAUAUGACCAGUCAUGACCAGCAGAUACCUUCUUUUAUCUUCCUGAGGCUUCUUCUCUGCUAUAUACCCUUGCCCCUUUGUAUCCUCCUGGAACAGUGACAUGAGCAGUUAAAUUACUGUCUCUAAGCCUCUGAAAUGAGUCAGAACUGGAAUUGAUUAAUGCCUCCAAGGGCAUUUUGAGCAUUAGGUCAAAAAUUUAUUGUUUAUUUUAUUUCCCAUGCAAACCAUAACCACAUCAUCCAACCCAGCUUACCAGAGAAGAUGAUUCAACUAGCCCAAAUAGGCCAUUAUGAAUAUUUGAAAAUUUAAGCUUCUAAAUUAAAAAAAACUGAUUAUGAAAGUAAUUAUAUUUAAAAACCAUUACUGUAUGUAGGGGGUAAUAUUAAUGCUUUUGGGUCAGGAUAUUAUCCCAAGAACUUUUGGAAUGAAUGUAACGUAAGUUGCUUCUUAUAUAAAUGGAGUAAAUUCAUCUGAUGAGUCCACUCAUGGGGAAAAAAAAAAGCCAGUUUUACAUAAGAAUGCCCUUAGUGAAGCAAUAAAAAUGAUGAAUUUUAUUAAAUCUUGACCUUUAAGUGCAUGUCUUUUAUUUAUUUAUUUAUUUGCCAAGACCAGCUUGUUUGGGGAGACCCUAACCCAGCAGCACUAGAGGAAUUAAAGACACACACACAGAAAUAUAGAGGUGUGAAGUGGGGAAAUCAGGGGUCUCACAGCCUUCAGAGCUGAGAGCCCCAAACAGAGAUUUACCCACGUAUUUAUUAACAGCAAGCCAGUCAUUAGCAUUGUUUCUAUAGAUAUUAAAUUAACUAAAAGUAUUCCUUACGGGAAACGAAGGGAUGGGCCGAAUUAAAGGAAUAGGUUGGGGUAGUUAACUGCAGCAGGAGCAUGUCCUUAAGGCACAGAUCGCUCAUGCUAUUGUUUGUGGCUUAAGAAUGCCUUUAAGCGGUUUUCUGCCCUGGGCGGACCAGGUGUUCCUUGCCAUCAUUCCGGUAAGCCCACCACCUUCCAGCGUGGGCGUUAUGGCCAUCAUGAACAUGUCACAGUGCUGCAGAGAUUUUGUUUAUGGCCAGUUUUGCGGCCAGUUUAUGUCCAGAUUUUGGGGGACUUGUUCCCAACAUUUAUUUAUUUAUUUUUAUUUUUUGGUAGAGACAGGGCUUCUCCUUGUUGGCCAGGCUGGUCUCGACCUCCUGACCUCAGGUGAUCCACCCACCUUGGCCUCCCAAAGUACUAGGAUUACAGGCAUGAGCCACCAUGUUCGGCCAGUGCAUGUCUUUUUAAUAUUCUGUGUGACAAAAAUAAGAGUAAAAUACCUGUGCUACACAUCAUAGUAUAACAGGAGUCUCACAGUGCUUGUGUGAUUGAGUUGUGAGCUGAACUUGCUGCUUUUUCCAUGGAAUACUAUUUUUACUUAAAAAAAUCUGACAAACUAUGCUUACUCUGUCUUGUGUUUUUGUCAACAAUUUUUGUGAAAACAAAGUGAGCCUGUCACUUUAAGAGACAGAAUUUGUUGCCAAUGAUAAAAAUCUCAGCUUUCAAGCGAAAAGUGAAAUUUUGGAAAACGAAUAUCCACCACAUUGAGCUUGACAACUUUGCAAUACUUAAAAGACUUUCCUGAGGAGAUUGGUGGUAAUAUUAACAAAUGUUACUGUUGACACUGAAUAAAUGCAGAAAUAAUGACAUGGAAUAAUGUUUUUAGUUUGUUUAUCAUUUGUUUUUAUAAUUCUAAAGAAGGAAGUGUUAAGUACUGGAGACAGCAAUUUUUACAAGUUAAAUACUUUUUUUUUUUAGUUGAAAAGUUCUACAAGUGAAGUUUCUUUAAUAUACUUUGAGUUCUAGGGUACAUGUACACAACGUGCAGGUUUGAUACAUAGGUAUACAUGUGCCAUGUUGGUUUGCUGCACGCAUCAACUCAUCAUUUACACUAGAUAUUUCUCCUAAUGCUAUCCCUCCCACAGCCUCCCAUCCCCGACAGGCCCUGGUGUGUGAUGUUCCCUGCCCUAUGUCUAAGUGAUCUCAUUGUUCAAUUCCCACCUAUGGGUGAGAACAUGCAGUGUUUGGUUUUCUGUCCUUGUGAUAGUUUGCUGAGAACGAUGGUUUCCAGCUUUGUCCAUGUCCCUGCAAAGGACAUGAACUCAUCCUUUUUUAUGGCUGCAUAGUAUUCCAUGGUGUAUACGGUGCCACAGUUUCUUAAUCCAGUCUAUCAUUGAUGGACAUUUGGGUUGGUUCCAAGUCUUUGCUAUUGUGAAUAGUGCCACAAUAAACAUACAUGUGCCUGUGUCUUUAUAGCAGCAUGAUUUAUAAUCCUUUGGGUGUAUACCCAGUAAUGGGAUGGCUGGGUCAAAUGGCAAUUCUAGUUCUGGAUCCUUGAGGAAUUGCCACACUGUCUUCCACAAUGGUUGAACUAAUUUACACUCCCACCAACAGUGUAAAAGCAUUCCUAUUUCUCCACAUCCUCUUCAGCAUCUGUUGUUUCCUGACUUUUUAAUGAUCGCCAUUCUAACUGGCAUGAGAUGGUAUCUCAUUGUGGUUUUGAUUUGCAUUUCUCUGAUGACCAGUGAUGAUGAGCAUUUUUUCAUGUGUCUGUUGGCUGCAUAGAUGUCUUCUUUUGAGAAGUGUCUGUUCAUAUCCUUUGUCCACUUUUUGAUGGGGUUGUUUUUUUCUUGUAAAUUUGUUUGAGUUCUUUAUAGAUUCUGGAUAUUCGCCCUUUGUCAGAAGGGUAGAUUGCAAAAAUUUUCUCCCAUUCUGUAGGUUGCCUGUUCACUCUAAUGGUAGUUUCUUUUGCCAUGCAGAAGCUCUUUAGUUUAAUUAGAUUCCAUUUGUCUAUUUUGGCUUUUGUUGCCAUUGCUUUUAGCGUUUUAGUCAUGAAGUCCUUGCCCAUGCGUAUGUCCUGAAUGGUAUUGCCUAGGUUUUUUUCUAGGGUUUUUAUGGUUUUAGGUCUAACAUUUAAGUCUUCAAUCCAUCUUGAAUUAAUUUUUGUAUAAGGUGUAAGGAAGGGAUCCAGUUUCAGCUUUCUACAUAUAGCUAGCCAGUUUUCCCAGCACCAUUUAUUAAAUAGGAAAUCCUUUCCCCAUUUCUUGUUUUUGUCAGGUUUGUCAAAGAUCAGGUGAUUGUAGAUGUGUGGUGUUAUUUCUGAGGCCUCUGUUCUGUUCCAUUGGUCUAUAUAUCUGUUUUGGUACCAGUACCAUGCUGUUUGGUUACUAUAGCCUUGUAGUAUAGUUUGAAGUCAGGUAGCAUGAUGCCUCCAGCUUUGUUCUUUUGGCUUAAGAUUGUCUUGGCAAUGUGGGCUCUUUUUUGGUUCCAUAUGAAAUUUAAAGUCGGUUUUUCCAAUUCUGUGAAGAAAGUCAUUGGUAGCUUGAUGGGGAUGGCAUUGAAUCUAUAAAUUACUUUGGGUGGCCAUUUUCACGCUAUUGAUUCUUCCUAUCCAUGAGCAUGGAAUAUUCUUCCAUUCGUUUGUGUCCUCUUUUAUUUCAUUGAGCAGUGGUUUGUAGUUCUCCUUGAAGAGGUCCUUCACAUCCCUUUUAAGUUGGAUUCCUAGGUAUUUUAGUCUCUUUGUAGCAAUUGUGAAUGGGAGUUCACUCAUGAUUUGUCUGUCUGUUAAUGGUGUGUAGGAAUGCUUGUGAUUUUUGCACAUUGAUUUUGUAUCCUGAGACUUUGCUGAAGUUGCUUAUGAGCUUAAGGAGAUUUUGGGCUGAGACGAUAGGGUUUUCUAAAUAUACAAUCAUGUCAUCUGCAAACAGGGAAAAUUUGACUUCCUCAUUUCCUAAUUGAAUACCCUUUAUUUCUUUCUCUUGCCCGAUUGCCCUGGCCAGAACUUCCAACAGUAUAUUGAAUAGGAAUGGUGAGAGAGGGCAUCCUUGUCUUGUGCCCAUUUUCAAAGGGAAUGCUUCCAGUUUUUGCCCAUUCAGUAUGAUAUUGGCUGUGGGUUUGUUAUAAAUAGCUCUUAUUAUUUUGAGAUACAUUCCAUCAAUACCUAGUUUAUUGAGAGUUUUUAGCAUGAAGGGCUGUUGAAUUUUGUCAAAGGCCUUUUCUGCAUCUAUUGCAAUAAUCAUGUGGUUUUUUGUCGUUGGUUCUAUUUAUGUGAUGGAUUAUGUUUAUUGAUUUGUGUAUGUUGAACCAGCCUAGCAUCCCAGGGAUGAAGCCAACUUGAUCAUGGUGGAUAAGCUUUUUGAUAUGCUGCUGGAUUCGGUUUGCCAGUGUUUUAUUGAGGAUUUUCGCAUCAGUGUUCAUCAGGGAUAUUGGUCCAAAAUUUUCUUUUUUUGUUGUGUCUCUGCCAGGCUUUGGUAUCAGGAUGAUGUUAGCCUCAUAAAAUGAGUUAGGGAGGAUUCCCUCUUUUUCUAUUGAUUGGAAUAGUUUCAGAAGGAAUGGUACUAGCUCCUCCUUGUACCUCUGGUAGAAUUCGGCUGUGAAUCCAUCUGGUCCUGGACUUUUUUUGGUUGGUAAGCUAUUAAUUAUUGCCUCAAUUUCAGAGUCUGUUAAUGGUCUAUUCAGAGAUUCAGCUUCUUCCUGGUUUAGUCUUGGGAGGGUGUAUGUGUCCAGGAAUUUAUCCAUUUCUUCUAGAUUUUCUAGUUUAUUUGCAUAGAGGUGUUUAUAGUAUUCUCUGAUGGUAGUUGGUAUUUCUGUGGGAUCGGUGGUGAUAUCCCCUUUAUCAUUUUUUAUUGCGUCUAUUUGAUUCUUCUCUCUUUUCUUCUUUAUUAGUCUUGCUAGCAGUCUAUCAAUUUUGUUGAUCUUUUCAAAAAACCGGCUUCUGAAUUCAUUGAUUUUUUGAAGGGUUUUUUGUGUCUCUAUCUUCUUCAGUUCUGCUCUGAUCUUAGUUGUUUCUUGCCUUCUGCUAGUUUUUGAAUUUGUUUGCUCUUGCUUCUCUAGUUGUUUUAAUUGUGAUGUUAGGGUGUCGAUUUUAGAUCUUUCCUGCUUUCUCUAGUGGGCAUUUAGUGAUAUAAAUUUCCCUCUACACACUGCUUUAAAUGUGUCCCAGAGAUUCUGGUACGUUGUGUCUUUGUUCUCAUUGGUUUCCAAGAACAUCUUUAUGUCUCCCUUCAUUUUGUUAUUUAACCAGUAGUCAUUCAGGAGCAGAUUGUUCAGUUUCCAUGUAGUUGUGCGGUUUUGAGUGAGUUUCUUAAUCCUGAGUUCUAAUUUGAUUGCACUGUGGUCUGAGAGACAGUUUGUUGUGAUUUCUGUUCUUUUACAUUUGCUGAGGAGCUUUACUUCCAAUUAUGUGGUCAGUUUUAGAAUAAGCAUGAUGUGGUGCUGAGAAGAAUGUAUAUUCUGUUGAUUUGGGGUGGAGAUUUCUGUUGAUGUCUAUUAGGUCUGCUUGGUGCAGAGCUGAAUUCAAGUCCUGGAUAUCCUUGUUAACCUUCUGUCUCAUUGAUCUGUCUAAUAUUGAGAGUGGGGUGUUACACUCUCCCAUUAUUAUUGUGUGGGAGUCUAAGUCUCUUCGUAGGUCUCUAAGGACUUGCUUUAUGAAUCUGGGUGCUCCUGUAUGGGGUGCAUAUAUAUUUAGGAUAGUCAGCUCUUCUUGUUGAAUUGAUCCCUUUACCAUUAUGUAAUGGCCUUUUUUGUCUCUUUUGAUCUCUGUUGGUUUAAAGUCUGUUUUAUCAGAGACUAGGAUUGCAACCCCUGGUUUUUUUUUUUGCUUUCCAUUUGCUUGAUAGAUCUUCUUCCAUCCCUUUAUUUUGAGUCCAUGUGCAUCUUUGCACGUGAGACGGGUCUCCUGAAUACAGCACACUGAUGGGUCUUGACUCUAUCCAAUUUGCCAGUCUGUGUCUUUUAAUGGGGGCAUUUAGCCCAUUUAUAUUUAAGGUUAAUAUUGUUAUGUUUAAAUUUGAUCUUGUCAUUAUGAUGUUCGCUGGUUAUUUUGCCUGUUAAUUGAUACAGUUUCUUCAUAGCAUUGGUGGUCUUUACAAUUUGGCCUUUUUUUUCCCGUGGCUUGUACGGGUUGUUUCUUUCCAUGUUUAGUGCUUCCUUCAGGCGCUCUUGUAAGGCAGGCCUGGUGGUGACAAAAUCUCUCAGCAUUUGCUUGUCUGUAAAGGACUUUAUUUAUCCUUCACUUAUGAAGCUUAGUUUGGCUGGAUAUGAAAUUCUGGGUUGAAAAUUCUUUUCUUUAAGAAUGUUGAAUAUUGGCCCAUACUCUCUUCUGGCUUGUAGGGUUUCUGCCGAUAGAUCUGCUGUUAGUCUGAUGGGCUUCCCUUUGUGCAUAACUCAACCUUUCUCUCUAGCUGCCCUUAACACUUUUUCCUUCAUUUCAAGUUUGGUGAAUCUGACAAUUACGUGUCUUGGGACUGCUCUUAAGUGAAGAUUUUAAAAAUCAUUUUUUUUUAAAUUUGAAAAUUGGAAUAAGAUAAAAGAUAACCACAGCUAUCGAUCAAUGAGUGAAAAGAAGUCUUGGUUUUUCAAUUGGGAAACACGGAAAAAAAUGUAUUCAGGAACAUGAAAAAUGCCUUAAAAACCUAUCAAGGAAAUUAUGAUUAUUUUGCAUUACUCAGAAUAUUAAACUGCCUGAAAUUUGUUAACGUAUUCUAUAUAUUUUUAUUGAGCAUUUACUAUGUGCCAGGAAUUAUUUUGGGCAAAUGGGAUAUAGCAAUGAAUGGAAGUCACAAAAUUGCUGCCACCACAGGGCUUACAUUCUAAUUCUAGUGUGGAAUUAUAACAGAAAUGCUUUAGCAAAAUGUAAACCACUUCAAGGAAGCUUUUAUUUCUCUGUUUUGUGGACGCCUCAUAUGAUAGAAUUUACCUCGUGAAUCUCUGUCACUCUAUUUGAAACAUGAAAUGUGAUACAAGUGGAUUGUAUUUAUAGAGUAUAUUAAAUGGGCUAUAUUAUUAAUGAGAUGUGUUAAAAGUACUAAAAGUUCACAUUUGAAGUGAGCUGGCAAGUCCAGAAUAAGUCCUUUUAAUUUUUAUACCAGUGUUUAUUCCUGUUCCCCGGGAGAGGAGGCAUUUUUUUCUGUCAACACUGGGCGAUUUAAGAACUGACUUGGGGGAUGAAAAUAACUAUGGUGAGUCCACAGGGGCAAACAGUUCUGCUCCAGCCAAUCCACAUCUGUUCACCUUAAGUAGAGAGGCUGGGGUGAGUCAAUAUUUACUCAGCCUCAGUGCCUCAGAAAAGGUGAUGAAUUUUAUCUUAUGAGCUGCUUUCAGUCAUCAUGUAUAUAGUUCACACACCAUUAAUAAGAAGACUCAUUCACCAUGGAAAUAAUCUGCUAGUCUGAGAGAAUGUUGGUCCCUAAGACAAGCAUCUUGAAGUAUCAAAGUUUCAUCACAGAUGUUUACUACUUCCUGUUUCUGUGGUCUAAAAUUCACCUCAAAUGUGUAGUUAACCUGUAAGUGAUGAACCACUUCCAUCACUUCCGCAAUAAAAUUAAAACGUGUCUGCUGGGGCACCCCCUCCCCA